GGGACAUCCCUGAGGGAAGGGCCGGGAGCGGGAGCGCCCCAGCGGCCGGCGGGCGGGCGGGCGAGCGGACGAGCGGCGCGGAGCCGGCCCGAGGCGCGCGCCGAGGGAGCCCCGUCCCCGGUCGUGGGGGCACCGCCCGCAGGCUCUGCGGGGUGGGCAGCUCCCGGGCCUGCCAUGAGCUCUCCGCCGCCCGCCCGCAGUGGCUUUUACCGCCAGGAGGUGACCAAGACGGCCUGGGAGGUGCGCGCCGUGUACCGGGACCUGCAGCCCGUGGGCUCGGGCGCCUACGGCGCGGUGUGCUCGGCCGUGGACGGCCGCACCGGCGCUAAGGUGGCCAUCAAGAAGCUGUAUCGGCCUUUCCAGUCCGAGCUGUUCGCCAAGCGCGCCUACCGCGAGCUGCGCCUGCUCAAGCACAUGCGCCACGAGAACGUGAUCGGGCUGCUGGACGUAUUCACUCCUGAUGAGACCCUGGAUGACUUCACGGACUUUUACCUGGUGAUGCCGUUCAUGGGCACCGACCUGGGCAAGCUCAUGAAACAUGAGAAGCUAGGCGAGGACCGGAUCCAGUUCCUCGUGUACCAGAUGCUGAAGGGGCUGAGGUAUAUCCACGCUGCCGGCAUCAUCCACAGAGACCUGAAGCCCGGCAACCUGGCUGUGAACGAAGACUGUGAGCUGAAGAUCCUGGACUUCGGCCUGGCCAGGCAGGCAGACAGUGAGAUGACUGGGUACGUGGUGACCCGGUGGUACCGGGCUCCCGAGGUCAUCUUGAAUUGGAUGCGCUACACGCAGACGGUGGACAUCUGGUCUGUGGGCUGCAUCAUGGCGGAGAUGAUCACAGGCAAGACGCUGUUCAAGGGCAGCGACCACCUGGACCAGCUGAAGGAGAUCAUGAAGGUGACGGGGACGCCUCCGGCUGAGUUUGUGCAGCGGCUGCAGAGCGAUGAGGCCAAGAACUACAUGAAGGGCCUCCCCGAAUUGGAGAAGAAGGAUUUUGCCUCUAUCCUGACCAAUGCAAGCCCUCUGGCUGUGAACCUCCUGGAGAAGAUGCUGGUGCUGGACGCGGAGCAGCGGGUGACGGCAGGCGAGGCGCUGGCCCAUCCCUACUUCGAGUCCCUGCACGACACGGAAGAUGAGCCCCAGGUCCAGAAGUAUGAUGACUCCUUUGACGACGUUGACCGCACACUGGAUGAAUGGAAGCGUGUUACUUACAAAGAGGUGCUCAGCUUCAAGCCUCCCCGGCAGCUGGGGGCCAGGGUCUCCAAGGAGACGCCUCUGUGAAGAUCUCUGGGCUCCGGGGUGGCAGUGAGGACCACCUUCACCUUCCACCUGAGAGGGGACUCUCGUUGCCACCUUGACCUUGGCUGGGGCUUGCAUCCCAAGGCAUCCAUCAGAGCAGACGCCCGGGUUCCAUGGACCCUCCUCCCCACGGCCAUGCCUCUGCUCUUGGGCGCCCAUCAUGGAGGAGCACCUGAACUUUCUGGACAAGACCUCUGGCCGACCUGGGGAUGGCCUCUGAUCCCUGGAGCAGUGGCCCACUUGCCCGGUGCUCUCAGAAACCUCAGAGCUGGUGGGGCUCCAGAUCAGGCCUUGGCCUCUGAGCCCUGCCUGCUCUGGGCCAUGCAGAGGAAGGACAGAGGGUGGGCGCAGGGCACCAACUCAGGGACAUCCCCUCUCCUGGGCGACGUCAGUGGACCUUCCUGCACCCCCAGCCUGGAAUGUAAAUCAGCUGUGUGGUGCCCGCGUGGCUGGAAGGAAAUAGACCCUUUUGUAGCUCCCUG